AGUCAGCACCCGCUGCGCCUGUCCCCGGCUCGUCCAGAGCCUUCCACCCCCUGCCGCCUUCCUUCCCCAAGCCACCCCCAACCUCUCCUAAGAGGCGCCGCCCCAGUCCCGGCCGCCGAACACUCCCUCGCCCAGCAUUCCCCUCCCCCGCCGCCCCCCAGCCCCCGCUGACGCCACAAAGUCCCUAGGCCUCCCGACCCCAGGUCCCCACGCCCCGGGCCGGGCCGCAGCCUCCUGGGCUUCGUGGGGGCAGACCCAGCCUUUCCCGGCAGCGAGCGCUCGGCCAGGUGCACUAGGCGCUGUGCGGGCCCCCCUUCCCCGCGGUGAGUAGCCCCCACCCCGCCGCCUAGGCUACCCUCCUGUGGCGCCUGGGCCACGACCUAAGCCUAACCCGGUCCUCCUCGCCCUCCAACGCCCGGCCUUCCCGCCUCCGCCGGCCGCCGCGUCCCUGGAGGGGCUAGCGCGCUUCAACAAGGAGCCAUGGAGGCUGUGGAACUCGCCAGAAAACUGCAGGAGGAAGCUACGUGCUCCAUCUGUCUGGAUUACUUCACAGACCCUGUGAUGACCACCUGUGGCCACAACUUCUGCCGAGCCUGCAUCCAGCUGAGCUGGGAAAAGGCGAGGGGCAAGAAGGGGAGGCGGAAGCGGAAGGGCUCCUUCCCCUGCCCCGAGUGCAGAGAGAUGUCCCCGCAGAGGAACCUGCUGCCCAACCGGCUGCUGACCAAGGUGGCCGAGAUGGCGCAGCAGCAUCCUGGUCUGCAGAAGCAAGACCUGUGCCAGGAGCACCACGAGCCCCUCAAGCUUUUCUGCCAGAAGGACCAGAGCCCCAUCUGUGUGGUGUGCAGGGAGUCCCGGGAGCACCGGCUGCACAGGGUGCUGCCCGCCGAGGAGGCAGUGCAGGGGUACAAGUUGAAGCUGGAGGAGGACAUGGAGUACCUUCGGGAGCAGAUCACCAGGACAGGGAAUCUGCAGGCCAGGGAGGAGCAGAGCUUAGCCGAGUGGCAGGGCAAGGUGAAGGAGCGGAGAGAACGCAUUGUGCUGGAGUUUGAGAAGAUGAACCUCUACCUGGUGGAAGAAGAGCAGAGGCUCCUCCAGGCUCUGGAGACGGAAGAAGAGGAGACUGCCAGCAGGCUCCGGGAGAGCGUGGCCUGCCUGGACCGGCAGGGUCACUCUCUGGAGCUGCUGCUGCUGCAGCUGGAGGAGCGGAGCACACAGGGGCCCCUCCAGAUGCUGCAGGACAUGAAGGAACCCCUGAGCAGGAAGAACAACGUGAGUGUGCAGUGCCCAGAGGUUGCCCCCCCAACCAGACCCAGGACUGUGUGCAGAGUUCCCGGACAGAUUGAAGUGCUAAGAGGCUUUCUAGGUAAGUGGGCACCCAGGGCCAGGACCUCUGACCCAGGAUCUCUUGGCGAUGCCCCACUGUACCCCCUAGCCUCGGAAGCCACCAAUGGGGGGGGUUCUACAAGUGCACUGCCUGGUGACGGUCACUGGCUAUUCACUGUGCCUUCGUAGGGCGGCGUUACUGGUGGUUCUAAUUCAUGGGAUGAAUCUUGUUGAGUUCCCAGUGGUCUCUCUGCCCAGCCCCCUGUACCUUAUUGCCACCAAGGCCCACACACAAUUGGUGUGUGGAAGCAUCAAGUAACCCCAGAUUCACAGCAGGGGAGGCCUCUGCGGAGUUAGGGGACCAUUGGCCACAUCCACCACUAGGGCCCGGGGACUCCCACCUUUGACCC